AGUGCGCGUGCGUGGAGCUGGGAGCUAGGUCCUCGGAGUGGGCCAGAGAUGGCGGCGGCCGACGGGGCUUUGCCGGAGGCGGCGGCUUUAGAGCAACCCGCGGAGCUGCCUGCCUCGGUGCGGGCGAGUAUCGAGCGGAAGCGGCAGCGGGCACUGAUGCUGCGCCAGGCCCGGCUGGCUGCCCGGCCCUACUCGGCGACGGCGGCUGCGGCUACUGGAGGUUUGGGCCGCGUCCGCGCUUUCCCCUUCCCUCUCCCCGCCUCCCCGGUCCCCAGACUGGCUCGUGCAAGCCGAGUCCCGGGGCCCGGGGGUCGCGUCAACUCCGCUGGCGUAUGUGUGCAGAUUCUCCCCGAGUCGGAGAGGGAAUCCGCCCAGCCAGCCGCCUUGUCAAAGCGUCCUGUCCACGACCACAGAGCGUUCCUCUGUCGCACGCGGGCCUCCUGACCCCCAGCCCCGGGCCUUCUUCGCUGCACCUCGGCUGCUGGCAGCUUCGAUUUUUCGUUUAGGGAUGCAGCCGCCCCGGCCGGGAGGUGUCAGCCACUGCCAGGUGUCAGGGCCUCAGCUGUCCCGGAAAGAGGAGUUAGACUAGUUCUUGAUUCUGGCCUCUAUACCUAGAACUAGUUGAUGGAAGAGGCAGAUCUUGGUGUUUGUUAGGGAGAGCUUUCAACAAUUAGAGUUGCCAAAAGUGCAAUGGAUUGCUUCUCAUGAGCUUCCCGUUACUAGAAGCGCUCAAAUAGGAACUGGAAGAACGCUUACUUAUGUGGAGGAGAGGAGAUUCAGCAAUCAGAAUCUCCUACUCAGCAAUCAGAAGAAGGGACUGGAUAGUAAACCUUUAAGAUUCUAAUCCAUAGAUUCCAUGAGUCUAUUUCUUGGACAUGUGACCUCUGCGAUUUCUUGGCAAAAACUAGUUGCUCAAAACGUGUUUAUUGAUUGAAGUAAAUUAAGGACUGAUCUCUCAUUGCAGAUUAUUCUCUUAUAGAAUUUGCCACUGGGGUCAACUAAUAAUCUUUAACAGGAUACUUAAAAUAUAGUUUGGUUGACAGGCAGUUCUUCAGGGCUGCCUCUAUAACAUGAAGUACAUGUGUUCCUAAAGCUCUAUACUGCCCUUUGUCGAGCACAGUUUAGAGCUGUAUUACUCUUUUUUAUCAGCCAGAUGUAGUGAGAGUGAGAAGAGUCUGAGGCUGGCAGCAUGUCUUGAUGUUCAUACUAACACCGAAACUGCAAAUUCCAGCUACUUUUGAUGGCAUGGCUAAUGUAAAAGCAGCCCCAAAGAUAAUUGACACAGGAGGAGGCUUCAUUUUAGAAGAGGAAGAAGAAGAAGAACAGAAAAUUGGAAAAGUUGUUCAUCAACCAGGACCUGUUAUGGAAUUUGAUUAUGUAAUAUGCGAAGAAUGUGGGAAAGAAUUUAUGGAUUCUUAUCUUAUGAACCACUUUGAUUUGCCAACUUGUGAUAACUGCAGAGAUGCUGAUGAUAAACACAAGCUUAUAACCAAAACAGAGGCAAAACAAGAAUAUCUUCUGAAAGACUGUGAUUUAGAAAAAAGAGAGCCACCUCUUAAAUUUAUUGUGAAGAAGAAUCCACAUCAUUCACAAUGGGGUGAUAUGAAACUCUACUUAAAGUUACAGAUUGUGAAGAGGUCUCUUGAAGUUUGGGGUAGUCAAGAAGCAUUAGAAGAAGCAAAGGAAGUCCGACAGGAAAACCGAGAAAAAAUGAAACAGAAGAAAUUUGAUAAAAAAGUAAAAGAAUUGCGGCGAGCAGUAAGAAGCAGCGUGUGGAAAAGGGAGACGAUUGUUCAUCAACAUGAGUAUGGACCAGAAGAAAACCUAGAAGAUGACAUGUACCGUAAGACUUGUACUAUGUGUGGCCAUGAACUGACAUAUGAAAAAAUGUGAUUUUUUAGUUCAGUGACCUGUUUUAUAGAAUUUUAUAUUUAAAUAAAGGAAAUUUAGAUUGGUCCUUUUCAAAAUUCAAAAAAAAAAGCAACAUCUUCAUAGAUGAAUGAAACCCUUGUAUAAGUAAUACUUCAGUAAUAAUUAUGUAUGUUAUGGCUUAAAAGCAAGUUUCAGUGAAGGUCACCUGGCCUGGUUGUGUGCACAAUGUCAUGUCUGUGAUUGCCUUCUUACAACAGAGAUGGGAGCUGAGUGCUAGAGUAGGUGCAGAAGUGGUAGGUCAGCUACAAAUUUGAGGACAAGAUACCAAGGCAAACCCUAGAUUGGGGUAGAGGGAAAAGGGUUCAACAAAGGCUGAACUGGAUUCUUAACCAAGAAACAAAUAAUAGCAAUGGUGGUGCACCACUGUACCCCAGGUUCUAGUCAUGUGUUUUUUAGGACGAUUUCUGUCUCCACGAUGGUGGAAACAGUGGGGAACUACUGCUGGAAAAAGCCCUAAUAGCAGAAAUAAACAUUGAGUUGUACGAGUCUGA